GGGAGGGGACUGAGCUGAGGCCCGCGGGCCCACCCGAGCAGGGGCCCUCGCUGUCACCGCCUCUGCCCCUGUCUCCCAGGCCCCAUGUCGCGCUUUUUCCCUAAACGAACCGGUGACAGGGCUGACCUGCCCGCACUCUGCUGGUCCCUACGCCGGGAAGGAGAAAGUCUCACGAAGCUCUUUCCUUUGCAACCCCUGUCCCCUUGCCCUCUGCAGCUCCACACAGCAUUUUUACUUCCCGUUUGCCUCCUCGAAUCCCUUCGGUGCUAAUCCAGCCCUUCGCCGUUUCCAGUUUGGGUCUGGCCUGUUUGUAUCCAAAUCGAAUUACACAAAACCAGGCCCUCAGUUCUGCCUCUGGCCCUCUUUCCGGAGACGGGCCCUGCCUCCUCCUGUGCCGGGCUGGGCUUGCCCGGCAUUGGCCGCCCGGAGCUCCCAGGGAGCAAGGCUGUGGUCCCGAAACUGGGCCCUCCGCUCAGCGCCGGGCAAGGCUCAAACCCCGGGUCUCUGACUUAUCCGGUCACGAAGGGACUGCUCAGAGCCUAACAGCCCUAAAAUUUGGUAUUGGCCCCCUCCCGGGAAAUCCUUCUCCCUACCAAUCAGGCAUCGCGGCAGGUGCUCUGCCAUCAUAGAGGCUCUGACACGCUGAACUCUCGAAGCUCGCGGCAGUGUUUAUUUUUAGGAGAGAUUUAGUUGAUCGGGAACCAAUUGACUUGGUUGACUGCCUCAUCUAGUGCGCACCUGGGCCGGGCCCCGCCGGGAAGGCGUGCUGGACGUUCUCAGUGAGCUCCGAGACCUACAGAAGAAACAGCUGCAAGGAUCCGAUCAGCUAGCUGUGAAGAAAGCCUCAGAUACGCUGUGGGGGCCAAGGAGCGAGCUCUCCCUUCUCCUGCUCUCAGCCUCAGUGAUCAAGGCUUCAGUGAACUGCACUGGAGCUCCCAGCGGGGGAUCUUGUCCCCUGUCCCGACUUUUGUGCUGCACAUUGGAUCUGGUGACACUCAGGAAAUGCUUGUCUCCGGCUGUUAAGGAAUAAUUUCAGAGUACUAUGGAUCAUGCUGAAGAAAAUGAAAUCCUUGCAGCAACCCAGAGGUACUAUGUGGAAAGGCCUAUCUUUAGUCAUCCGGUCCUCCAGGAAAGACUACACACAAAGGACAAGGUUCCUGAUUCCAUUGCGGAUAAGCUGAAACAGGCAUUCACAUGUACUCCUAAAAAAAUAAGAAAUAUCAUUUAUAUGUUCCUACCCAUAACUAAAUGGCUGCCAGCAUACAAAUUCAAGGAAUAUGUGUUGGGUGACUUGGUCUCAGGCAUAAGCACAGGGGUGCUUCAGCUUCCUCAAGGCUUAGCCUUUGCAAUGCUGGCAGCUGUGCCUCCAAUAUUUGGCCUGUACUCUUCAUUUUACCCUGUUAUCAUGUAUUGUUUUCUUGGAACCUCCAGACACAUAUCCAUAGGUCCUUUUGCUGUUAUUAGCCUGAUGAUUGGUGGUGUAGCUGUUCGAUUAGUACCAGAUGAUAUAGUCAUUCCAGGAGGAGUAAAUGCAACCAAUGGCACAGAGGCCAGAGAUGCCUUGAGAGUGAAAGUCGCCAUGUCUGUGACCUUACUUUCAGGAAUCAUUCAGUUUUGCCUAGGUGUCUGUAGGUUUGGAUUUGUGGCCAUAUAUCUCACAGAGCCUCUGGUCCGUGGGUUUACCACCGCAGCAGCUGUGCAUGUCUUCACCUCCAUGUUAAAAUAUCUGUUUGGAGUUAAAACAAAGCGGUACAGUGGAAUCUUUUCCGUGGUGUAUAGUACAGUUGCUGUGUUGCAGAAUGUUAAAAACCUCAACGUGUGUUCCCUAGGCGUCGGGCUGAUGGUUUUUGGUUUGCUGUUGGGUGGCAAGGAGUUUAAUGAGAGAUUUAAAGAGAAAUUGCCGGCGCCUAUUCCUUUAGAGUUCUUUGCGGUCGUAAUGGGAACUGGCAUUUCAGCUGGGUUUAACUUGAAAGAAUCAUACAAUGUGGAUGUCGUUGGAACACUUCCUCUAGGGCUGCUACCUCCAGCCAAUCCGGACACCAGCCUCUUCCACCUUGUGUACGUAGAUGCCAUUGCCAUAGCCAUCGUUGGAUUUUCAGUGACCAUCUCCAUGGCCAAGACCUUAGCAAAUAAACAUGGCUACCAGGUUGACGGCAAUCAGGAGCUCAUUGCCCUGGGACUGUGCAAUUCCAUUGGCUCACUCUUCCAGACCUUUUCAAUUUCAUGCUCCUUGUCUCGAAGCCUUGUUCAGGAGGGAACCGGUGGGAAGACACAGCUUGCAGGUUGUUUGGCCUCAUUAAUGAUUCUGCUGGUCAUAUUAGCAACUGGAUUCCUCUUUGAAUCAUUGCCCCAGGCUGUGCUGUCGGCCAUUGUGAUUGUCAACCUGAAGGGAAUGUUUAUGCAGUUCUCAGAUCUCCCCUUUUUCUGGAGAACCAGCAAAAUAGAGCUGACCAUCUGGCUUACCACUUUUGUGUCCUCCUUGUUCCUGGGAUUGGACUAUGGUUUGAUCACUGCUGUGAUCAUUGCUCUGCUGACUGUGAUUUACAGAACACAGAGUCCAAGCUACAAAGUCCUUGGAAAGCUUCCUGAAACUGAUGUGUAUAUUGAUAUAGACGCAUAUGAGGAGGUGAAAGAAAUUCCUGGAAUAAAAAUAUUUCAAAUAAAUGCACCAAUUUACUAUGCAAAUAGCGACUUGUAUAGCAAUGCAUUAAAACGAAAGACUGGAGUGAACCCAGCAGUCAUCAUGGGAGCAAGGAGAAAGGCCAUGCGGAAGUACGCUAAGGAAGUCGGAAAUGCAAAUAUGGCCAACGCAACUGUUGUCAAAGCAGAUGCAGAAGUAGAUGGAGAGGAUGCUACCAAGCCUGAAGAAGAGGAUGGUGAAGUAAAAUAUCCCCCAAUAGUGAUCAAAAGCACAUUUCCUGAGGAAAUGCAAAGAUUUAUGCCCCCAGGGGAUAACGUCCACACUGUCAUUUUGGAUUUCACUCAAGUCAAUUUUAUUGAUUCUGUUGGAGUGAAAACUCUGGCAGGGAUUGUAAAAGAAUAUGGAGACGUCGGUAUAUAUGUAUACUUAGCAGGAUGCAGUGCACAAGUUGUGAAUGACCUCACUCGGAAUAGAUUUUUUGAAAAUCCUGCCCUAUGGGAGCUGCUGUUCCACAGCAUUCAUGAUGCAGUUUUAGGCAGCCAACUUAGAGAGGCACUUGCUGAACAGGAAGCCUCGGCUCCCCCUUCCCAGGAGGACUUGGAGCCCAAUGCCACUCCUGCCACUCCUGAGGCAUAGAUGAGGACCUCACCCUAGGAUGGGGUUAUAAGCCUCUCAUGAAGUUCAUAAUUUACACGUUUUAAAUACUAGACGCUAGAUUUUUUUUUCUAAGGGUGAAUACUAGUAGUCCAGGCUUGAUUUGGAGGGUGAAUGACGCCUAGCAAGAUGUAUUGUACUUGUGUUUUUUUAAUUGAAUACUUCAAAGAUAAA